GGAGACCUGGGAGAGUCCGGCCGCACGCGCGGGACACGAGCGUCCCACGCUCCCUGGCGCGUACGGCCUGCCACCACUAGGCCUCCUAUCCCCGGGCUCCAGACGACCUAGGACGCGUGCCCUGGGGAGUUGCCUGGCGGCGCCGUGCCAGAAGCCCCCUUGGGGCGCCACAGUUUUCCCCGUCGCCUCCGGUUCCUCUGCCUGCACCUUCCUGCGGCGCGCCGGGACCUGGAGCGGGCGGGUGGAUGCAGGCGCGAUGGACGGCGGCACACUGCCCAGGUCCGCGCCCCCUGCGCCCCCCGUCCCUGUCGGCUGCGCUGCCCGGCGGAGACCCGCGUCCCCGGAACUGUUGCGCUGCAGCCGGCGGCGGCGACCGGCCACCGCAGAGACCGGAGGCGGCGCAGCGGCCGUAGCGCGGCGCAAUGAGCGCGAGCGCAACCGCGUGAAGCUGGUGAACUUGGGCUUCCAGGCGCUGCGGCAGCACGUGCCGCACGGCGGCGCCAGCAAGAAGCUGAGCAAGGUGGAGACGCUGCGCUCAGCCGUGGAGUACAUCCGCGCGCUGCAGCGCCUGCUGGCCGAGCACGACGCCGUGCGCAACGCGCUGGCGGGAGGGCUGAGGCCGCAGGCCGUGCGGCCGUCUGCGCCCCGCGGGCCGCCAGGGACCACCCCGGUCGCCGCCUCGCCCUCCCGCGCUUCUUCGUCCCCGGGCCGCGGGGGCAGCUCGGAGCCCGGCUCCCCGCGUUCCGCCUACUCGUCGGACGACAGCGGCUGCGAAGGCGCGCUGAGUCCUGCGGAGCGCGAGCUACUCGACUUCUCCAGCUGGUUAGGGGGCUACUGAGCGCCCUCGACCUAUGAGCCUCAGCCCCGGAAGCCGAGCGAGCGGCCGGCGCGCUCAUCGCCGGGGAGCCCGCCAGGUGGACCGGCCCGCGCUCCGCCCCCAGCGAGCCGGGGACCCACCCACCACCCCCCGCACCGCCGACGCCGCCUCGUUCGUCCGGCCCAGCCUGACCAAUGCCGCGGUGGAAACGGGCUUGGAGCUGGCCCCAUAAGGGCUGGCGGCUUCCUCCGACGCCGCCCCUCCCCACAGCUUCUCGACUGCAGUGGGGCGGGGGGCACCAACACUUGGAGAUUUUUCCGGAGGGGAGAGGAUUUUCUAAGGGCACAGAGAAUCCAUUUUCUACACAUUAACUUGAGCUGCUGGAGGGACACUGCUGGCAAACGGAGACCUAUUUUUGUACAAAGAACCCUUGACCUGGGGCGUAAUAAAGAUGACCUGGACCCCUGCCCCCACUAUCUGGAGUUUUCCAUGCUGGCCAAGAUCUGGACACGAGCAGUCCCUGAGGGGCGGGGUCCCUGGCGUGAGGCCCCCGUGACAGCCCACCCUGGGGUGGGUUUGUGGGCACUGCUGCUCUGCUAGGGAGAAGCCUGUGUGGGGCACACCUCUUCAAGGGAGCGUGAACUUUAUAAAUAAAUCAGUUCUGUUUA